AGAGAGCCCCGAGCCUCAGCCCUCCGCCCCCGGCCGCCCCCCCGAAGCCCCAAGCCGGGAGGAGGGUGGGGGCCGGGGGCGCCCACGCCGGCCCCAGACUCCAGUAGAGCCAAGGGACAGUGCCCGGGGAAGGGGGUGGGGGCGCCCCAAGAACGUGCCCGCGGCCGGGUCAGGGGCGUCCGGAGAGCGGCUGCCCGGGCCAGCGGAGUGGCCCCCGGGGCAGGUGAGUCGGCGGCGCCGCCCGAGUGGGGGCGUGCGCGCCAAAGUUCCCCGGCAGCGGCGAGCGCGCCCGACGCGUGGGGACCCGGGGCUGCUCGCGGCUGGAGAGGGGCGACAGAGGCGCUUGACGCGGCGGAGCGGGGGCACUAUGCCCUCCGAGGGCCGAGGGACCCCAGCCGGGAAAGGGGUGCCCGCCGGAUCCGACGGCACUGGUCCUCGGCGGCCGCGGCGAAGCAGGCGGCGGCGGCCGGAGCGCAGCCCCGGGACCCUGCACGGCGGCCGGCAGCGACAGCGGCGAAGGGACGCGGCGCCCCUGCGUGGGGACGUCCGGCCCGCGCCCGCGAGUGGGCGCCGACGGGGACCCGCGCCGCGCUCCCCCGUCACCGGCGAGCGGCCGGAGCCCUGAGCUCGCCUCCUGGAAGCCGCGGGUCGGCGCUCGCCCCGAGGGCGCCGGGACCUCGGCCGGGUGAACACAAACUGCUCUGCAAUUGAUUCGACCGCGCCGGGCGGGUGCGGGUGCGGGGCCCGGAGGGAGCGCGUGCGGAAGGCCGGAGGGCAGGAAGUCAGGCUUCUGCCGCGAGGGUGGCGCGGCCGCGCGGGGACAGAGCCUUCCUUAUUUAUGAGUCUGCCGGCGCUCGCCUGCUUCCUCCGAAGACUUCAGGGAGAGUCUGCGAGCUGCCGUCCCCGCGUGUGAGGCACAGAAGGGCUGGAUGUCAGAACCGCAUAAUUAUUCAUUAAACUACAAACUUUUUUUAACCCAAAGAAUAUCGGUGAUUUUUGUCCACUGCGAGGAGAAGAAGAGAGAGCCCAGGGCUCAUGAAAUGCAGCAGAAUCCUUAUUUAUAAACAGGCCGCGGUAGUGAUAUAUGCAACCCCAGUCUACUCAGUGAGUUUUCUAUCCUAUGGAUAUCGGUCUUGAGAGUUGAGAUUGGAGAGCAGCGCCGUCUGUACUGGGUCCUGCAGCCUCUGUCCUUUCAAUGCCUGGUUUUUUCUGUGACUGCUGGCCUUCCCUGGAGAUCAGAGCGCUCCUGUAUGCCAUGGGCUGUAUUCAGAGCAUCGGAGGCAAAGCCAGAGUCUUCCGGGAAGGGAUCACGGUGAUUGAUGUGAAAGCCUCCAUCGACCCCGUCCCCACUAGCAUCGAUGAGUCCUCCAGCGUGGUGCUCCGCUACCGGACACCCCACUUCCGGGCCUCGGCCCAGGUGGUCAUGCCGCCCAUCCCCAAGAAGGAGACUUGGGUAGUUGGCUGGAUCCAGGCGUGCAGCCACAUGGAGUUCUACAACCAGUACGGCGAGCAGGGCAUGGUCUGGCUCUGUCACCCAGGCUGGAGUGCAAUGGUAUGAUCUCGGCUCACUGCAACCUCUGCCUCCCAGGUUCAAGCGAUUCUCCUGCCUCAGCCUCCCGAGUAGCUGGGAUUACAGGUCCAGCUGGGAGCUCCCCGACCUCCAGGAGGGCAAGAUCCAAGCCAUCAGCGACUCGGAUGGGGUGAACUACCCCUGGUACGGCAACACCACAGAGACCUGCACCAUCGUGGGCCCCACCAAGAGGGACUCCAAGUUCAUCAUCAGCAUGAAUGACAACUUUUACCCCAGCGUCACAUGGGCCGUGCCCGUCAGCGAGAGCAACGUGGCCAAGCUCACCAAUAUCUACCGGGACCAGAGCUUCACCACCUGGCUGGUGGCCACCAACACCUCCACCAACGACAUGAUCAUCCUGCAGACGCUGCACUGGCGCAUGCAGCUCAGCAUCGAGGUGAACCCCAACCGGCCCCUGGGCCAGCGCGCCCGGCUGCGGGAGCCCAUCGCCCAGGACCAGCCCAAAAUCCUGAGCAAGAAUGAGCCCAUCCCGCCCAGCGCCCUGGUCAAGCCCAAUGCCAACGAUGCCCAGGUCCUCAUGUGGCGGCCCAAGUACGGGCAGCCGCUGGUGGUGAUCCCGCCCAAGCACCGGUGACAGCCAGGACCACCCGCUAGGUUAGACUCACAAAUAAUAAUACCGCUGAAAACAAAACUCAGACUCACUCUUCAGUCAUUCAGCAAGAUACAACCAUUCUACCCUCUCCAGCGGGCGGAUCUCACUGUGCUGAUGCCCCCGGGAAGGCCUCCCCGGCUCUCGGCACCUGCUUCCUUUCAGGGAGAGGGGAGAUCUAAGCAGGACAGACAGACCCCACGUGCGCCCUCAGGGUGACCUCUGGUCUCCUUGCCUCUCCUUUUUCUCAGUUUCAGUCGCUCACUUGUAACAGAUUCCCUGAAACACUGCUUUUUCCGUUUUUUAAAAAAACUCCUCUUUUGGGGGCUCAGGGGCAGGAGGAGGGGGAGCUGAUUAGGAGGGAAGCUCCAGCCCCCGAUCAAAGAGACAGAUCCACACUGCUGCCGAUUUGUGGCGCUGGCCGGCCUUCCCCCCAGGUCCCUCCGCCCUCUGUCAUGCGGCCUUAUGUAGACUUGCUUUGCCAAACUUUUGCCUUAAGCUGAAUUGAAAGGAAGAAAACCAAUCGGAGAAAGAAAGCAGGAUCUCUUUUCUACCGGACUUUUCCUCUUCUGCCAGAGGUGGAGGGAGGGUUGGGGUCGCCCGCGAGAGUCUCUUGAGCCCUUCUUCCCGGUUGUCUUGGGAGAAGGGUGAGGAUGGGCAUUUAGACCCGAAACCAGCUGCUCACUCUUUCUUUUUGGCAGAAAUAAAACCACAGGUAGAUUCUGCCUGAACAGCCCCUUCUCUCCCUCCACCCCCAGGUCGUAUCCCUGCACCUGCGGAGAGGGGCUGUGAGCUCUGGCGGGGGGUGGCUCCACCAGUCGCCUGGCCUCUUCUCCCCUCUCUUCCCAGCAGCCUUAACUUCCCUUGGGCGGCUCUAGGAGGAGAGAGGCAGGCUCCUGUGAGCCCAGGGAAUUUUCACCCUCUCAGUCCUCAGGACCCACCCCCAGUUGAGUCCCUGGCCCUUCCUCCAGGUGUGUGGCUUUUUCCUUCUCCAUCCACACUGGUCCCAAAUGCCUGGGGGCCGGCCACCUGGACCGCCGACACACAGCCUCAAUGUUAGUCUCAAAGGUAAGGAAGGCAUUCACGUCCCUUCUUGCAGGGCAUUUUAAGACUUGAAUCGGGUGGGCCCCGGCCCCUGUGGCUGGCUGGCCCCUGGUGUACUGUAAAAGGGCCAAGACAGGGCUCGUUCUCAGGGGCGCCCCUCCCAGGCCCUCAGGGCAGCGGGACGGUGCAGUCAGGCUCUGGGUGCCACAGUGAUGGAGGUGGAAGGCACCCAAGCUCUAGGGAAGUCUUGGGAGGCAGUCGGCCGAGCCCCUGCUUCCUGUCCUCAAAUAAGUGAAUCCAGGCCAAGGGCUGGGAGGGCUGGGUGGGCUUAUCGUCGAGAGGGUUCAGAGCCACUCUGGAGGCUGGGCUGGCACAGUGGAGAGCAACAGGUGAGGACAGACGUCUGGAAGCCCAUCCCUGGGACCUGCCCUCCCUCGGUCCCAGGUCACUGGAGCUCCAGGGCUUACUUAGUCCUGACCCAUUGUGCCAGGGUUCUGAGCAGUGUCGGCCUUGUGGCCACUUGCAGGGGCUAUUAGGGGACAUCCCGCUGAAGCCACGCUCCUUCCAGCUUGCCAAACCCACAGCUACCCGCCCGGGACCCACACUCAGCCUAAUAAUUAUCAAGCACAGAAAACCGUCCAUUUAGAAAAAUAAUCCAUUUCUGCUGCAGAUGAGCCACUUGUAAGAGUCUCCGUGACAGCGUGGGACGGUGUGGGAACCAAAGUCCCUGCCCUGCUCCUUUGUCCACGGGCUAUUGCGUUUAUUCAAGGGGUGCUUAAUGACCGUUUAGCCACUGCCGUCGGUCUCCGGGCCCAGCUCGUGCCAGGAGGCUGUCCUGGGACACACUGGGCUGGAGCUGCCGGCUGGCACGGUGCUCAGGGGGCCCCUGAUGGGGGCCAGGACCUCCCCGCAGAAACUGCAGGUUCUCUUGUGAGGAUGGAGGCCGUGCCACCCCGAAAGGCAGUAGCCUUAGGGGAACAGUGGGUCCCAGCUGCAUGUCUGAGGAUGGGUGGGGACAGGGCUGGGACUCAGCUUUCAUUCACUGGAGACUUCUCCACUCAGGUCUUUGUUGCACUAAAGCAGGGACAGGACCCUGGGGGUUCAGGAAGCGGGUCUCAGGCCGCUGGUUUAUUCCUGGAGGUGGGGCUGGAGACCAGAAUGGAAAGGGGCUUCCUGAGCUGCUAGGGGGUGAAGGACCCCCGAACCCGCAUUUCUUGAGUGAGAGCAAACACUCGAGGCAGGAGCCAGCACCCCUCCCACUGCAUGCCCGGCCCCCAGCCCACCUUGCCCCCUGACCCACCUUCACCCGUGCCCCUUCUUUCUGCCCUUCCUCACCGAAGAAGGGCUAGGAACACCCUGGAGAGGCUGCAGGUCCGGCCACGGACGCUCAGCUGAGCCCCGGUCUGCUCCUUCAGCCUCCUUGCUCAUGUUGGAGCACAGGCCCCAGGCUUCCUGCCAGGGCCCCGAUUCUUCUUAUGUCCUCCAGCCCCGCCCUGGCGUGGACAUCCACUCACUCCUUCCAGCAAUAAGAACCGUCCUUGGUCGUGGAGAGUACUGUGAAACAAACCAAUGCACUUACCAGGAGGCACAAGACUCUUGAAGAAGAUGUACAAUGAACCUUUUUUUUUUUACAAAAAACAAAAAGCAAAUAUUCAUAAAGAGAAAUAAAAUGUAAUUUUAAAGUA